GGCGUUGAAGAAGAGCUGCUUAAAGAGAAACAGGGACACACGCUGGCUUUUGGUCGGCUUUGCUCACCCACCAACAGCUAGGAGCUGGAAGGCUCAGAAGAGCUGGGGUGGGCAUGGGAGAGACAGAGGAACCCCGGUGGCUGGAAACACAGUUCCUUCCCAGGGUCUCUUCAGCUUGCUGGUUGGACCUCUUAGCCUGCUUAUGAAGCCUGAAUUGACAUCAUGCCAACUGGUCUCCUGCUGAUAAGUGAUUCCUUAACUUCCUCGGGAGCAGCAGAAACUUGUUUUGAAAAAAAUCAGAUUCUAAAUCUUUACAGCUGUUUACUUCUGCAAGCACAAUGGCCGUAGUAAGGAAUUCAAGUCACAGCGCAGCCGUGGCAGGGAAGGCUCUGCAUGGAGUCACAGGACAAAGCCUGUCCUGGAAACGUGCUGGAAGGAAGUCGGCCUCAUUCUUUACGACGGGCAGCAGCUCCAAAUGAGAAACCAAGGGGCUUGGCUCUGGACACAGAAUGUUCAGCUUAACAAAGAAAUGACACUUGCCAGCAACCGGAGCCUGGCAGAAGGAAACCUUUUGUACCAGCCCCAGCUGGACACGUUGAAAGCACGCUUGACCCAGAAAUACCAGGAACUCCAGGUUCUCUUUGAAGCCUAUCAGAUAAAGAAGACCAAAUUAGACAGACAGUCUAGCAGUGCUUCCUUGGAGACCCUGUUAGCACUUCUUCAGGCAGAAGGGGCCAAGAUUGAGGAAGACACUGAGAACAUGGCAGAGAAGUUUCUGGAUGGAGAACUUCCUCUGGAUUCCUUCAUUGAUGUCUAUCAGAGCAAACGGAAACUGGCCCACAUGCGACGGGUGAAAAUCGAGAAGCUCCAGGAGAUGGUCCUAAAGGGGCAGAGACUCCCACAGGCCCUGGCCCCGCUGCCCCCCAGGCUGCCCGAACUGGCACCUACCGCCCCCCUUCCCUACCCUGCCCCAGAGGCCAGUGGGCCUCCUGCCGUUGCACCUCGGCGCAUCCCCCCCCCACCACCCCCGGUGCCUGCGGGACGCUUAGCCACCCCGUUUACUGCGGCCAUGAGUUCGGGACAGGCCGUGCCGUACCCAGGAUUACAGUGCCCGCCCCUGCCCCCCCGCGUGGGCCUCCCCACUCAGCAAGGAUUCUCUUCGCAGUUCGUGUCCCCAUAUCCGCCACCUCUCCCUCAGAGACCCCCGCCCCGGCUCCCUCCACACCAGCCGGGUUUCAUCCUCCAGUGAGCGCCGGCGCGGUCCUUCCCGGGAGACUUCUUCCACCUGGCGUGUUGUGCUCUGCUCACGGGAAGGAGGCUGGAGGUCCGCUCUGUGCCAAGGGCUCUGGGGCCCUGGGCCAGCGUGUCUGUCUGAUUUUAGAACUGUAGGUCAGUGGUGAGUAGUAGGAGCCCAGGCUUUGGGCAUCAAGGCAGUUGUGUGUGCCGGGUUACAGCCUGACACCUGUGCGUUGCAUCGGUUUGCAUUAUCCGUGUGAUUUCUAAGUAUCUUAGCGUUGAUGAACUCAUGUUUGGGAAGAAAUAGGCCUCUCCCCCAGUCCCAUUUAGAAUCGUGGUCCUUCUGUUGCAGCUUUAUUUAAUGAGCAUGGUUCAUGAUACUUAUUUUAUUUUCGAAAGACAGUCCUAUGUGUCUCACCCACCGGCCACUGCAGCCCUGGUGAGGGCGGGUGGGCGCCGGCCGGCCUGGAAGAGCGCCGUGGCUGGGCCACCACCUGUGGCUGCGUUGUUGCUCACUGAAUCUGUUGGGGAGAGGUCACCAUAGUCACCGCCUGACCUGGCUGCUGCUCUUGCUUCAGAGCCACAAGCAAAGUUUGCACUGGGCCCACUGCCGAGUCCAGAGGCCGGAGAACGGCCACUGGUGUGGGAGGGGAGCGCACGAGUGGGACUUUGCACAGCAAAUUGUGUCCCCAGCUCCUCCUCUCCCGCCUGCCUGGAGCCGGCCCUGAAGGUUUCUAUGAAGAAAUAAUCCCCCAAUAUUUUUACUACGUGUGUGAUUUUCCUGUUUUAUAUUGAAAAAACUUUUUUGACACUCCCAAGACCAUUCAGGGAAAUUUUAUAAAAAAUGCAGAUACUGUCUUGAGCAGAUCGAAAUGCCGAUGAAGUGGAUGCAAUUUCCUUUUGUGCAAGCAGUGCACGGUGCCCCCCCCUCGGGUGUCCGUGCUGUGCCUUAGCUUCCCCAGGUGCCGGGACUCACACCUGCUAGGGGCUGGGCAAGGCCCCGGCUCUGCUUUCUCUGAAGGGCUUGUCCAAGUUCAUUGCCCUGUUACAGGUGGUCAAGACGUCCGGCCGCCUUGACCCAGGCUACCCUUAGCCAAUAUCCUCUGCCCCUGGGUGGCUGGUGGCUGGGCCUCAGGGUGGGCAACGUUAGGGGUUUGGCGAAAGCCCGCCCCAUGGGAUUGAGGGACGGGGCUGCACUCCAACCGUCUGCACCUGCUCUUCCCCCACCCCUGUGGGACCUCAUCUUCACGUGCCAUGUGUGCUGAAGGCCCAGGGCCCAGCAGGGGGCAGUGGCACCUGUUGACGGAAAAGGCCGAGGUGCUUACCAGUGGACCUUCUGGCCCGCCCCUCCCCUGUCACUUGUCGGGCAUCCAGGGCCCCGACCUGUGCCUAGCCGCCAGGGUGACAGAAGGCAGAACUGAAGCGGGGUCUGGGCCACGGGCCAGGCCACUGCCUUUUGUCCUCAGUGACCGUACAUUCCUGCUCUCGGACUUGAACUCUACUGUAACUGUUUUCUUAAAGGAAAUGAAGCUGUACAGGACGAUUCACUGCCAUGCCAGUCAGGCGGGCUUGCCAUGUUCUGUGAAUCUCGAGUGAGCGGUGCCACCCGCCCCCAUACCUCCGCCACCGGCCGCUGUCGGGGAUGCCACAGCCUGCCACGGUCGCAGCCAGACGUGAGCUUGGCAUUGAAGUUGCAAAGCGGCCCCUGGCCGGGCUCGCCGUCGCUGUCCAGGGCCGUGUCCGGUGCUGUGGCUGUAAAGCUGUAGGACCCUUUUUAAUAAAUAGAGAAUUAUUAAUAA